AUGGCAUUGAGAGGGUGCUGCCCGCUCAAUGCCCAGCAGCAGCUCUGGAAGGCAGUGCUCAGCCCCAUCACCACUGUCCCGUGGAUGCCUGUGUACCUCUUGCCUUUUCUGGGCUUGCGUUUCUCUCCUCUAGUGGGAUGUGUGGCCAUGUUUGGCAGAAGAGCCACAACUCGCUGCUCUAGGAGCCGACAUGACUCCUUCAUUUCUGUGCAUGCCCUGGGGACUAGGGUGGAGCCUGAGGAGAGGCUGCCAUGGAACACGCAGGCGUCACUGGACGCCUUCCGAGUUGGGGGGAGGAGAAAACAAAACCACAGGAAGAAACGAACAACGCUUUCGGGUGGGCCCGGGACCAUAGAGGGUCGCUCCGCCACUUUCCUAGAGCGACCGCGGCGGCGCCAGAGCGCGGCGAGGCCCUCACUUCCGGCGGCGCGGGAGGCGCCCAGCGAGCCAGAGUGGUGGCUGGUCCCGCGCGGUGAGUGGGAUUGGGGCACUUGGGGCGCUCGGGGCCUGCGUCGGAUACUCGGGUCCGCUCGGGAGCGCGCUGGCCGCAACGAGGGCGGCGCGGGCCCGGGCGAUGGCGUGGCUUGCGUCUCCCGCCUCCGGGCAGGGCCUGGCCGCCGGGCGGGGGCGGGAGGGCCACGCGGGCCCAGGGUGGGGCCGCGGCCUGCGCGGCGGGCGGGCCGGGUCAAUGAGGAGCGGCCGGCGGAGUGCUGGGAACGGGAGGCUUGGACUGGGGGCCCGGGCGAGGCGCGGCCCGCGGCGGGUGGAACUGGGCGGGUGAGCAGCAGCCCCGGCCCCUUCCGUCGCUCGGAGCGUUCGAGGACUAGAUACGUGGAACAAAUGCUUAGGCAGCACAGGGCUGCUCUGAGCGGUUUUCAGAUUCAGACUCAUUGCAACUUCUAACAUCUUGAUGGUGUUGCCACUUUAUCAUUACCCUCCCCAUUUUACGAGGAAACUGAGGCACAUUCCAGUUAGCUGGGUGUGCAAGAACAGCAGCUUCUGUCACUCAGGUUUAACUUCGUGCUUGCCCCUGCUGGGGAGCUAUGCAAAGCACGGGUCGCCGCGCUGGACUGAGCAAUGGAAGAUGUGGCUGCCACUAAGAGUACAGGCUCUGGAGUCAAACUGCUAGGGUCUGGGAACCCGGCCAGUGCCUUCUAGCAUUGUGCCCUCGUUUCCUUAACUUAAAACGGAAAUAACUGCAUAAAGGUGCCAGGAGAAUUAAAGAGCUAGCACAGAAUCAAGUUACACAGUGUCUGGCACAUACUAGUAUGAUUGCCUCAUCCGUAGGUGGAUUUGACAGUCUGAGUUUCUGACUAGAUCUGACUUCCAUUGUAUUAAAUGCGUGUGCUUUUAUGUAUAAUGACCAUUAUAGUUAUUAAAAAAAAAAAAAAGCAACACCAACACCAUGUACCUAACACAAUGUCUCCUGUGUGGUAGAUGUUCUGUAAAUAUUUGCUUAAGUUAAGGAGUGGGUAGUCCUAACUGUAAUCUUGUGUUAUAUGCGGCUUACUCUUACGCUGACCAUAAUUACAGCUGAUGUAAUUAUUAAAUAUCCAGAUAAAGUCCUGGACCUAAAGUCUCAAUUAUACAAUAAGAUGAAAGGAAGGCAAGAAAAAUUAUGUUUUUGUUUUCAUUUAUUUGCUUUAUAUGUUUGUAUGCAAAGAAACCCAGAAUAAUUGUUUCUAUUUUAAAUUCCACAUUCUGACACAAGAUAAUGAAAAAUAGUUCCAAUAAUUUUAUUGCUUUUGAAGUUCUAGAUUUUCCGACAUUGCCACCUAUGUGGGGUUUGUAGGGGUUUUUGUUGGUUUGUUUUGGCCGUUAUUUUAAAUAGCCACAAGUCAGCCUUAUAAAUAAAUAAAAUCAUUUGAAAUUUUGAA